GAGAACCCUUCCGGUGGGCUAGGUACUGAGCGCGCGAGGUGAGGAGUUGUGCAGGGUUUGGGGAAAGGAAGGCUGGCUUGGCGAGAGGGCAGGUUUGCGGGCUUUCGCCCCCUUUUCCAAAGACCAACAAAGAGUCCUUCCCCAACUCCCAACUCAACCCCUUUUGGAACUAUGUGUGGUGGUUGGGACCCUGUGGCGCAUCCUUGUCGCUCGUGUCCUUCUCAUGCCCGGCGACGCGUCUUUGUGGUAACGCCCUGCUGCCAUCUCUUUUCUUCUCUAUGCGAGGAUUUGGACUGGCAGUGAGAAUAAGAGACAACGAUUCACGUCUACUUUCUAGGAUGACUUCCAUGUGCUCCAUCUCGCGCGUCCCUGAGCAUGUUGAAUUUCCAAAUCCUAAAUAAGCCGCGCGGUGUAGUUUGUAUUAUGUUGCGUUUCUCUUUCUGCUUUCCUCGCCCUUUCUCCAUCAUCCUUUAGGCUCUACAGAGUGAAGGUUUAAAUCCAAGGUCAUGGCAAAACAUCUGAAGUUCAUCGCCAGGACUGUGAUGGUACAGGAAGGGAACGUGGAAAGCGCAUACAGGACCCUAAACAGAAUCCUCACUAUGGAUGGGCUCAUUGAGGACAUUAAGCAUCGGCGGUAUUAUGAGAAGCCAUGCUGCCGGCGACAGAGGGAAAGCUAUGAAAGGUGCCGGCGGAUCUACAACAUGGAAAUGGCUCGCAAGAUCAACUUCUUGAUGCGAAAGAAUCGGGCAGAUCCGUGGCAGGGCUGCUGAGGCCUGUGGGUGGGACACCCAGUGCGAAACCCUCAUCCAGUUUUCUCUCCAUCUCUUUUCUUUGUACAAUCCCAUUUCCUAUUACCAUUCUCUGCAAUAAACUCAAAUCACAUGUCUGCAAGAAGGCCUCCAAAUAUAGAAACAAUCCCAUUAGUCAGCAGUGGACCCUGUCUUUUAUUAAGUGAAAGAAGAAACUGAGUCUGAAAGUACUCUAGGAGUAGAAUGGUAUUUGCCAGGGACUGGAGGAGGGGGCAGUGAGGAGUUAUUGUUUAAUGGGUACAGAGUUUCAGUUUGGGCAGAUGAAAAAGUUCAGGAGACGAUGGCCUGGCAUGGUGGCUCACGCCUGUUAUCCCAACACUUUGGGAGGCUGAGGCGGGCGGCUCACUUGAGGCCAGGAGUUUGAGACCAGCUUGGCCAAUGUGGUGAAACCCCAUCUCUACUAAAAAUACAAAAAAAAAUUGGCCGGGCGUGGUGGUGCACGCCUGUAAUCCCAGAUACUUGGGUGGCUGAGGCAGGAGAAUUGCUUGAACUGGGGAGGAAGAGGUUGCAGUGAGCCAAGAUCAUGCCACUGCACUCCAACCUGGGCGACAGAGUGAGACUCCAUCUCAAAACAAAAAAACGGAGAUGGAUGAUGAAUGGUGAUGGCGGUUGCUCAAAAAGUUGAAUGUACUUAAUGCCACUGAACUAUACCCUUAAAUGGUCACGAUGGUAAAUUUUGUGUUUUACUACAAUAAAAACUUUUUUGAAAGUC